AUUAUCAGCUUUCUGGACACACAGACAGAGACAGACAGGAUGGACUUCCUCCGGCUAUACCUCCCUGGGCUGCACCAGGCCUUGAGGGGGGCACUGGAUUCCCUCGGCACCUUUGUCUCCUACCUCCUGGGAGAUGCAGUCCCCACUGUAGAGCGGGAGGCGCAGGCGGCUGAGGAACUGGGGGUGGUGGCGGUGGGAAAGACAGGGAAGAUUGUAGAGGAGGAAGCCCAGGAGGACCUGGAGGGCCUUAGAGGCAGCCAAAACGAGGGGGCUGGAAGGCUGAGAGGGCCUGGAGAUGACAGAAGACAUGAAGUGGGGAGCUCAGCUGUAGAACAGACCUGGGGCUGGGGAGAUGGCAGCUCCCAUGGGUCCCAAGCAGAGAGGCAGGACAGUGGGGCUGGGGAGACAGCCAAGGCUGCCAGGUGCCAGGAGCCAAGCGCCCACUUGGAGGCCAGAAAGAAAUCCAAGGCAGGGUCUGGGGCUUGCCAAGACAGGAGCGGCCAAGCCCAGGAGAGGCAGGAGUCCCAUGAGCAGGAAGUGAACAGAGAAGAGAGGCUGAGAAGCUGGGAACAGGAGGAGGAGGAGGAAGAGGUCAGGGCAAGAGAGCCAGGGAUGGCCAGAGGGGCGGAGUCAGAGUGGACCUGGCAUGGGGAGACGGAGGGGAAGGCUGGUGCUGUUGGGCCAAAGGCGGCAGGGGACAACCGGGAGAUGGAGCAGGGGGUCAGGGAGGCAGAUGCAGGGGAAACUGAGGAGCCUGGGGCCGAAGGGGCUGGGAAAGGAGAAGAGGUGGUAGUGGUGGAGAAGGCCUGUGAAAGCACUAGGGCAUGGGGGACGUGGGGCCCAGGGGCAGAGCCUGAGGACUGGGGAAUCUUAGGCAGAGAGGAGGCCAGGACAACCCCAGGUAGGGAAGAGGCCAGGGCAAUUUUAGAUGGGGAGGAAGCCAGGACAAUCUCAGGCGGGGAGGAGGCUGAGACAGCCUCAGGCGGGGAGGAGGCUGAAACAGCCUCAGGCGGGGAGGAGGCCGGGACAGCCUCGGGAGGGGAGGAGGCCGGGAUAGCCUCAGGCGGGGAGGCUGGGACAGCCUCAGGAGGGGAGGAGGCCGGGACAGCCUCAGGAGGGGAGGAGGCCGGGACAGCCUCAGGAGGGGACGAGGCCUGGACAACCUCAGGCAAAGAGGAGGCUGACCUGCUGGGAGUCAGACAGACAGAAUAUGGAGCAGUCCCAGGAGAAAGGCUCCUAGAGGCUACUGGAAAAGUCUGGGUCCUAGAGGAGGAGGGGGAUGAGGAGAGAGAGGCUGAGGUGAGCCCUUUCCCCAAACAGCCCCAGGUCCUGGGCACUGAAAGAACAGAAGAGGCUGCUGAGAGCCAGACCGCAGGGAGGGAAGCUGUGGGAGGCCAGGAGGCAGGGGAGAGCUUUGAGGGCCAGGUAGACCUGCGUGGUAAGGAGGCUGAGAUGAGGCAGGACUUGGGGAUCAGGGCCGACCGGGCCAGGAUGGAAGAGCUGGUACAGGCAGAGGAGGCCCAGGAGGAGAGAGGGAGCAGCAGGGAUCCAGUGGCUGAGCUGCCCUCAGAUGGAGAGGCUGAAGGCACUGCCGACUUGGAGGCAACUCCAGAGGCCAGGCCUGAGGAGGAGCUCACAGGGGAGGAGAGUGAGGCGGCCCAGACUAGCUGUGGCCUACUGGGCGUGGAAUGGGGUGGCCUCACACACAGCGUCACCAAAGGCCAAGGACCUGAGCUGAUGGGGGGCGCCCAGACCCCAACUAAGCAACCCGAGGAAAGGGAGGCAGGGGAGGUGGAGCUCAUGGGAGUUCUGGCCCUGAGCAAAGAGGAGCAGGAGAGGAGCCUGGAGGCAGGUCCCAGGCACGCGGGGUCUGUAAAGCCUGAGGCCUCCGAGGCCUUCCCAGGAGCCUGGGAAAACCGCACGAGAAAGGACAUGGAGAGAGGAAAUACUCAGGAGGAUGCGGCCGAUGGCGAGCAGCGGGAGGAGGAGGAGACUGCGGGAGGCCAGACCCUGGCGGCUGAGGCUGAAGGAGACCGAGAGUCUGAACUAUCAGAAGUCCCAGAGGCAGGCGGGGAGGGGCUGACAACCCAGGACGCGGGAUGUGGAACUGAGGAGGGAGAGGCAUCUGUCUCAGAGAACCAGGAGCUGGACGGAAGCACAGGGGCAGACGCAGGGCCUUGCCCGUCACUGGGAGAGGCCUAUGCCAGAGAAACUGAGGAUGAGGAGGCGGAGGCUGACAGAACAUCCAGAAGAGGCUGGAGGCUGCAAGCGGUGGCUGUGGGCCUCCCGGACCGUGAGGAUGCACAGACUGGCUCUGUGGCUGCUGGGAUUAUGGGGGGUGAUGUGGUCCCACACAUCAGCGCUGCUGGCGCUGGUGAAGCUUUGGAAGGGGUGCUUGGGCAAGGCUGGGACUCGAAAGAAAAGGAAGAGGCAGCAGCAGGAGAGCAUGCAGGUGGGCAAGAAUUUGGUCUGGAGGGCUCAGCAGAGGAAGAGGUGACUGGCAGAGGCAGCCAAGUAGAGGCUUUUGAGUCCAGGGAGGGAGGACCUUGGGGAGGGCGGGUAGAGGCCGAGGAAUCUGCAGGCGCAGAGGACAGCUGUGGGCUGGAUCCCGCGGGCUCCCAGACAGCGAGGGCAGAGGGGAUGGGAGCCAUGGUGGAGGCUGGGGGGCUUCUAGAAAAGUGGACGCUGUUGGAAGAAGAGGCUGUUGGAUGGCAGGAGAGAGAACAGAGGGAAGACAGUGAGGGGCGGUGUGGGGACUACCACCCUGAGGGAGAGGCACCAAGGCUCCUUGAUGCAGAGGGUCUCAUGGUGACCGGGGGCCGGAGGGCAGAGGCCAAGGAGACUGAGCCAGAAAGCCUGGAACAUGUCAGGGGCCAGGAGGAGCAGCCAACACACCAGGCCCCUGCAGAAGCUGCGCCGGAGUCAGUCGGGGAAGCCGAGACGGCUGAGGCCAUGGGCAGUGCCAGAGGAGGUGCUGCCAACAGCUGGAGCGAGGCCCCGCUCCCCGGGUCCCUCCUAGACGUCUCUGUCCCAAGGAGUCGCGUGCACCUCUCGAGAAGCUCCUCACAGCGUCGCUCCCGGCCCUCUUUUCGUCGGACUCCGGCCUGGGAGCAGCAGGAGGAGCCCCCAGCCCCCAACCCUCCUGAGGAGGAGCUGUCAGCUCCUGAGCAGAGACCCCUCCAGCUGGAGGAACCCCUGGAGCCAAGCCCUCUGAGGCAUGAUGGGACCCCGGUGCCAGCCAGGAGAAGGCCCCUGGGACACGGGUUUGGCCUCGCGCACCCUGGCAUGAUGCAGGAGCUGCAAGCCCGUCUGGGCCGGCCUAAGCCCCAGUGACUGAGACCCGGUGCUCUGGGAGCCAGGCCCUGAGUGGGUGCCAGAAGGCUUGCUCCAAUGCCACUGAGCCCUGCUCCCUCUGCCACUGUGGACACAUCCUCUCCACCCUCUGGGCCUCAGUGUCUUGAUGUAUCAUUCAUGGAGCAGGCAAAACCAGACGUCUGGGAAGACCGUGAACUUAAGGAGUCUGAUUCUCCGACACAGGCUGGUGGACCACCUACCCCACUGAGACCACCUCUCAGGGUGCCUGCCCUGGUUCCUCCCCAGCCUGAGUCAGCUGUCUGGACUGCAAGGAGGCUGGGCACGGGGGCUCACGCCUGUCACCCCAGAGCUUUGGGAGGCCAAGGUGGGAGGAUCGCUUGAGACCAGGAGUUCGAGACCAGCCUGGGCAGCAUAGCAAGAUCCCCAUCUUUUAAAAACAAAAUAAAACAAUAAAGACUGCAAGGAAGACUGAGGGAA